ACUGUGCUGAGAACUGCUCUCUCUGACCGGGUCUCCUGUUUCUACCUGGUUUGUUGUGAACCUGUGUUCUCCACAUUUGUCCUGACUCUUCAGGUGAAUAACUGAGCCUUUCACUUGGCUUUGCUGCAACCCUUCAGCUCUGUGCGUGAUGUAGACUGGAACUAUGUACAAAAUAAGCUGGUCAACAGCAAAUCGUUGGAAGAUCAACAGGCACAAAACACGAUAAAAUUGAAUCUCACAAACUGAUUAAAACAUUAAACUAAAAUGCAGACUUACAUUGCUCUGCUUUCAUAAUAAAGACCACUAGAUGGCGCAACUUAAGUCUACUACUUGUUAAAAGACAUUGUCAGAGGCCUAAUGACAGACCGACCUCCUCUUUGAAGAAAAAAACUAGUGAGGGAAACAAGAGAGGGGAAUGUUAUGAAUACCUGAAGUUACACAGUCCUUCUCUCGCAAAGGCAGAGGCGUGCUGAGUGCAGUUUGGAAGCAAGAAUUGGAUAAGACUUCUCAGGCGUCUGCACAAUCCCUAAUGGCCCCCAGAUCUGCCAAGGAGACCUUCAGGAUAAACCCAAAUGUAGCAGCAAAUUUUGCCAGCAAACGAGAAGAGAUCCUGGCUGGGUUUCCAUGUUGCAGAUCAGCUCCUUCUGACGUGAUCCUAGUAAGAGAUGAAAUAGCUCUUCUGCACAGAUACCAGUCACAGAUGCUGGGUUGGAUUUUGAUCACCUUGGCAACCAUUGCUGCCUUAGUCUCCUGCUGUGUGGCAAAGUGCUGCUCUCCCCUCACCUCUCUGCAACAUUGCUACUGGACCAGCCACCUCCAGAAUGAGAGAGAACUCUUUGAACAAGCAGCAGAGCAGCACUCUCGGCUCCUCAUGAUGCAUCGCAUAAAGAAGCUAUUUGGCUUCAUUCCCGGGAGUGAAGACGUCAAACACAUCCGCAUUCCUUCUUGUCAGGACUGGAAAGAUAUUUCAGUACCCACUCUUUUAUGCAUGGGUGAUGACUUGCAAGGUCACUAUAGCUUCCUUGGAAAUAGGGUGGAUGAGGAUAAUGAGGAAGACAGAUCAAGAGGUAUUGAAUUAAAACCUUGAUUACAGCACCUUUCAUGAGUCAGGUUGCUUAGCAGAUACUUGGCUUUUAUGGCUUUUAUGAUCAGGCCAUUUCAAUGUAAUCUCUUCAUCUUUUUCUUUCUCUCUGAUAUUUGUUUACGUAAGUCCAUCUCAAAUAUUAUUUCUAAAAUCAAUCUAUUAGAUAAUUGUGCCAAUCUCUCAUUUUGAAAUUUUGCCAAUGGUCUGGUAAUGCCUAGAGUGGAAUGUGAAGUCACAUGGAAAUUUGCAUCUUAGUUCUGUUACUUAGUAGCUGUGUGAAAAUUAAUAUUUCUGAGUGCCAUUUUGUCAUCUGCACAUUGUAGCUACCUCCUAGAGCUAUUAUGAGAAUUAAACAUGAUAAUACAAAGUGUUUAGCACAGUGUCUUUCAUAAAAAUAGAUGCUAAUGAAUGUUACUUUCUCUCUUUCUCUUUUGCAUUCCAUGUCUUCUAUUCACCAUUUUCCCUGCCUCUAUUUUCUGGUUUUAUCAGUUUCUACCUUUAUAUAAUGUCCAGAACUUUUCACAGCCUCCCCCUCUUUCUUCAGACCUAAAUAUCUGACCUUUUGGGAAGCAGGACAGAAACCUCUUUCUAAUCCAGUAACAUGUGAGGGAGAAGCCCAUGCAGGAAGCUCUUGAGUUACUGUACUAUAACCUGGGGACAAUGAUAUAUUAUUUAUCAUUAUUAGUAUCAUGUUAUUUGUAGCACCUCCAUACUAGGAGCAUUUUUAUGGCCACUACAUAUAAAGUUUCUUCUAGAAAGCUUCUCCACUGUGCUCUACUCCAGAGAUACCAUUUGUACCUUUUCAUUACCAAAUUGCACCUUUGCACUCAAAAUCCAUUUGUGAAACCAAAACUGCAGUCUGUACUUGUAUAUCCAUUAUCUGUAACUACAAAAGAGGAUAAUUCCUGCUUGGUGUUGCUCUGCCUGGCUUUACUAAAUGCAGCCUACAGUAUCUGGACAAUUUUCUAAUUUAUCUAGAUUAUUUCUGUGAUAUAUAGUGACUCGUGCCUGAUUUUUGCUACGUUCACUGAAGCAACUUGCUCAUUAGCAAAAAUAAGUUGUCUGAGGGCAUUCUGUCUAUUUAUUUCUUCAGUCAAAACAAUGCUUACUGGACAGUGGACCAACUGCCAAUAGUCAAUCCAAUUUUCAAGAUUCACUUUCAAGGAGACCAAGGAACUUGACUAUACUAUCUAAAAUGCAAUCAAUUACUUGGUAAUCUACUUUUACACAAUUAUGGAAGGUUUUAUUUUCUAUAAAGUUCUGGGUCCUUGAACUUAAUAGGAAGAAGCAGAAAAUGAAUUUUUAAGAAAUCAAAAUGUUUUCAGGUUUUGUUUUGUCCUUCAAUAAGAGACUGCAUAUUGUAGCUCUUUGCUGGGACAGGAGAACUGUCCUGCCCUCACCAUUACUCAUCUGUCAUUUGACCUUGGACAAAUCAGUCCAUCUCUCUGGACCCUGGAUUUUUUUCAUCUAUACAAUAAAAGGGAUGAUAAUAUUUUACCUCUUGGAAGAAAAUAACUGAACUAAAUAACUGCUUAAGGUCUCUUUUACAUCAAGUACGAUUUUUAUGUUUAUGUUUAUAUAUAUAUACAGGUCAAUAUGCAUACAUCUUUCUGAAAUGGUAGUAGACCCACGUUGCUUCUCUUGGAAGGAAAAUGUCCCCAACUCUGAAUCUGAGCUUUCUCUGAAAACAUUUACUGGCAUUCCACUUUUAAAAGAAUGUUAAUGUACUGAUCUUUUUCAAGUCAUCAAGGAAAGCCAUUCCAGUUUGUCUACUAACUCUACACUCAGUACUGAUAUGACAUUACAUGAAGGAUGUUAAAAAUACAAAUAGAAGUAUGUUGUGGAAGGCAACUAGGGUUCUAGUUCCACACUGAUACAAAUGAACUGUGUAAAUAUGGAAUGUCACAUCCAUUUUGUUCCCUAAGGUCUGCUCCAGUUCUAAAAUUCUGUUCCUAUAUAACUGAUAAUUUUUUAUAUUCUUCUGUAUUGGAACAUACUAGUUAAAUGAACACUUUCAACCAUGCUCAGAAUUAGUUUAUUAGUUGUCAGGAACUAUACCACAGUAAAGACUCUUCAAUAAGAUUUUCGGUUAACAACAAAAUCAAAGAAUAUUUGAAGUUAUAGCAUUACAUCAUCAGAAAGAAGAUUAAUAGUUGUUUAUACCCUAAUACCAGGAAACUAUUUCCACUAGCUUCUGAAGCCCUUCUACAUCAAACUCUUUUAGUGUAUGAUGUAAAAAUUUUAUAUUUUGAGCCAGUUAAUCAUGAUCUUCCCCUAUAACUUUCUGGCAAAGGAUUCUAAGUAUUCGUUGGCUCUUCUACAUGGCUUCAGAAUGAUUUAUAGCAUCUAUGUGAACAUUUAAAAGGUAGUACACACCCCUGGGAUUUCAUCUUACAGUACAUUAUCUAUCUCAGAUCAAAUAAAUGGAAUUUUUAGUAUUUUGGGGGGGGGGGGGGCUAUGGUCUAUAGCAUUUUUUUGCUCCACAGCUAGUUAAAUGAAACUUUUUCAUUAAGAACAUGGUACUCCCUCCCCUUUAUGCUUAAUGGAUUUAUGUAAUUAUAAAACAUAUAAUUAAAGUCAAUUAUGUGCUAAUACUACUUUAUAUUUUGCUACCAAAUGCUUUUGGCUACCACAUCAAACCCUGGAGCUUGACAUAUAUAAACCUGCUCCUUUCUUAAUUUCAUUAGCUCCUCCACGGUCCCAUCAUGACCUAAGUUGCCACCUUCCCAGGAGACAAAUACAAACCAAUGUGUAAAUGUGUUUUACUCAGCUUUCUUUAUGUUUUCCAAAGCUGAAUUGUAGAACCGCAUUUAUACUCUGUCCUUCUCUGUGUCUCUUUUCUCUGUUCUCAGUCUUCCAUUCAUUUUUUGUAGAAAUUCUAAUGCAUGAUUGUAAUAAACAACAGUGAGAUUUUGCUA